GUCCAGCCACAAAGGUGACAGCAUUUAACAAAGCUGCCAAGAAAAUUCAGAGUUAAACAGUGAAAACUUGAGACUGGUUUGCUGGAAUCUGAGGGUGGCCACUGCUGGGUAAUAAUUUGAGCCAAGAAAACAUUCCGGGAACUCCUCCAACACCGUCAUGAAGAAGGCUUAGAGAAACCUCCAGGAGACUGCUACCAUGGCAGAGAAGCCCAAGCUCCACUACUCCAAUAUACGGGGCAGAAUGGAGUCCAUCCGGUGGCUCCUGGCUGCAGCUGGAGUAGAGUUUGAAGAGAAAUUUAUAAAAUCUGCAGAAGAUUUGGACAAGUUAAGAAAUGAUGGAUAUUUGAUGUUCCAGCAAGUGCCAAUGGUUGAGAUUGAUGGGAUGAAGCUGGUGCAGACCAGAGCCAUUCUCAACUACAUUGCCAGCAAAUACAACCUCUAUGGGAAAGACAUAAAGGAGAAAGCCCUGAUUGAUAUGUAUAUAGAAGGUAUAGCAGAUUUGGGUGAAAUGAUCCUUCUUCUGCCCUUUAGUCAACCUGAGGAACAAGAUGCCAAGCUUGCCUUGAUCCAAGAGAAAACAAAAAAUCGCUACUUCCCUGCCUUUGAAAAAGUCUUAAAGAGCCACGGACAAGACUACCUUGUUGGCAACAAGCUGAGCCGGGCUGACAUUCACCUGGUGGAACUUCUCUACUACGUGGAAGAGCUUGACUCUAGCCUUAUUUCCAGCUUCCCUCUGCUGAAGGCCCUGAAAACCAGAAUCAGUAACCUGCCCACAGUGAAGAAGUUUCUACAGCCUGGCAGCCCAAGGAAGCCUCCCAUGGAUGAGAAAUCUUUAGAAGAAUCAAGGAAGAUUUUCAGGUUUUAAUAAACCAGCCAUAGAGGUCAAGAACAUGCAAGACCAGUAUUCUAAAGUUUUGCAACAAUUAAGUGCUUUACCUAAGUGUUGAUUGUGCCUGUUGUGAAGCUAAUGAACUCUUUCAAAUUAUAUGCUAAUUAAAUAAUACAACUCCUAUUCACCCACUUAGUUAAAAUUGAUUUCUUCUCAUUAGGAUCUGAUGUGAAUUCAGUUUUCCAAUCUCCUCCUAGCCAACAAUUUUCUUGGAAUUACAAAUUCAGUAAAAAUGGAAACUAUAAAUUAUGUGGUUUGUUUGACUUUUCCAAGAAUUGCCCUGUAACAUACAAUUUGUCAUACAAUCUAUUAAAAUGCCAAUGUAAAAAUGCACCUCUGACAUUUUCAGGUAUGCACAGGAGAAGAGUUACCAUCCUGGAUAAUGGCAUAAAGACAUUUUCUUCUUUUCCUGAACAGUCAUUUUAUUUCUGAUAAAAGCAUUCUUUCUAAUGCAUUUGCAAAACAA